ACUCCUCGUCUCACCCAUGAGAGCGAGCUGCCUUCUGUCUGGUUGGGCGAUUCCUGCAGGGCCUGAGCCUCCGCAGAGCCCGGCGUUCAAGGAGAAAAAAGGAGCCGCGGAUGUGAGUUUGCUUCGUCACUGCCUUGUGAGCGACUUUGGGCAAGUUACUUAGCUCUCCUGACCUCAGAUUUCUUGUCUAAUGUGGGAGGGAACCGAACGUGGAUGACGCUCCGGGCAGCGGCGGAGAGCCGAGAUCACCGCGCGCGCCUGAGAACUUUGUCCGAAGCGCGGCCCGGGGACUGGGAGCGCAGGGCAGGGAGCUCCCUCUGCGGGAGCGCGGAGGCGCUCCUACUUUCUCCGCACGUCACGGGGGCCGCUCAGCGCUCUCCCACCCCGGGCCGGGCGAGAGCGGCUCCCCAGCAGGGCGACGGAGGAGCGCGGCGAGAGCGAGCCGCCGCGGAGAGCCUGGGAACCCAGAGCGCAACCCUCGGCCCCCGCCGGGGCGGCCUCCGCAGCCGCACGGACCCCGCGUUCGGGGCUGGCCCGCUCCCUCUCGGCCCAUGUUCUAGAACUACAUCCUCGGUCACUGUCCCAGUACAGCCAUCUGUAGCACCUCCUCAGUAACUGACGGUGAUGUUCCUUUCCCUACGCUGUUUAUACCAUCAGCCUGGGGUUUUCUUUGGAGGUGACACAAAGAACAAUAAGAAUGUAAGGUCAUCUAGGCAAGAAACCUGUCUUUCCACUCCUCUGCAUGACUCCUGGAGUGCUGUGGGAGUGUGGAGGAACUGCAUCUGACUGAGUCAUCCUCCCACCUAAUGGUCUCACUCCAGAACAUCCCCUGGGCUUGGCAGUGAGCGAGUCACCAAGGGAGAAUCAGUGACUUCAUUGAAAUCAAGGAGCUGCAGUAGCAGGAUGUUAGCUUAUUCAACUAGAUCAGGAUGCUUUUUAAAUGAAGAUAUUCAAAUGUUAUUUUAAACAUACCCUACAGCAGAAAGUUUUCAUCCUGUUUUUAACCCUAUGGCUGCUCUCUUUGUUAAAGCUUCUAAAUGUGAGACGACUCUUUCCGCAAAAAGACAUUUACUUGGUUGAGUACUCCCUAAGUACCUCGCCUUUUGUAAGAAACAGAUACACUCAUGUUAAGGAUGAAGUCAGGUAUGAAGUUAACUGUUCGGGUAUCUAUGAACAGGAGCCUUUGGAAAUUGGAAAGAGUCUGGAAAUAAGAAGAAGGGACAUCAUUGACUUGGAGGAUGAUGAUGUUGUGGCAAUGACCAGUGAUUGUGACAUUUAUCAGACUCUAAGAGGUUAUGCUCAAAAGCUUGUCUCAAAGGAGGAGAAAAGCUUCCCAAUAGCCUAUUCUUUGGUUGUCCACAAAGAUGCAAUUAUGGUUGAAAGGCUUAUCCAUGCUAUAUACAACCAGCACAAUAUUUACUGCAUCCAUUAUGAUCGUAAGGCACCUGAUACCUUCAAAGUUGCCAUGAACAAUUUAGCUAAGUGCUUCUCCAAUAUUUUCAUUGCUUCCAAAUUAGAGGCUGUGGAAUAUGCCCACAUUUCCAGACUCCAGGCUGAUUUAAAUUGCUUGUCGGACCUUCUGAAGUCUUCAAUCCAGUGGAAAUAUGUUAUCAACUUGUGUGGGCAAGAUUUUCCCCUGAAGUCAAAUUUUGAAUUGGUGUCAGAGUUGAAAAAACUCAAUGGAGCAAAUAUGUUGGAGACGGUGAAACCCCCAAACAGUAAAUUGGAAAGAUUCACUUACCAUCAUGAACUUAGACGGGUGCCUUAUGAAUAUGUGAAGCUACCAAUAAGGACAAACAUCUCCAAGGAAGCACCCCCCCAUAACAUUCAGAUAUUUGUUGGCAGUGCUUAUUUUGUUUUAAGUCAAGCAUUUGUUAAAUAUAUUUUCAACAACUCCAUCGUUCAAGACUUUUUUGCCUGGUCUAAAGACACAUACUCUCCUGAUGAGCACUUUUGGGCUACCUUGAUUCGGGUUCCAGGAAUACCUGGGGAGAUUUCCAGAUCAGCCCAGGAUGUGUCUGAUCUGCAGAGUAAGACUCGCCUUGUCAAGUGGAAUUACUAUGAAGGCUUUUUCUAUCCCAGUUGUACUGGAUCUCACCUUCGAAGCGUGUGUAUUUAUGGAGCUGCAGAAUUAAGGUGGCUUAUCAAAGAUGGACAUUGGUUUGCUAAUAAAUUUGAUUCUAAGGUGGACCCUAUCUUGAUUAAAUGCUUGGCAGAAAAGCUUGAAGAACAGCAGAGAGACUGGAUCACUUUGCCCUCAGAAAAGUUAUUUAUGGAUAGAAAUCUCACUACCACAUCAUGAUAGUAAAAUCAGGAUGGAAAUAAGAGGGUGCCUGAUAAAUGGAGUCAGUGUGGAAUUGAAUACCAUACUAUGCCCAAUACUGUUUAAACUCAGUCCUCCCAUAUUUUAAAAGGUGUCCAAAAUUCCAUACACAAGGGAAAGUGAUCUAGCCUUUGAUGUUAUUAGCCUGCAGUUGGCUAGGUUUUUUUAAUAUUUGUUUUUGCUUGUAAUCUCACUGAGCCAAAUCAGAGAUCUUAAACAUUCAGUCAGUCAUCAAACAUUAUUGAGCACCUAACUAUAUGACAGGCACUUUUUUAGAGACUGCGGCUUAUCCUCAUCAUAGCAACCUCGGUAUCUUUAAGUUCUCCACAUAACAGUCAGGAUUCUACUGAAGAAGCUUUUGAAGUUUGUGGUAAUCGUCUGAUCAUAUAAACCACCCAUUUCAGAGUAGUGUUUAAGUACUGUGACCAACACUCCACUUGUCUCUUAACUCAGCUUUCAAGACAUUUCUUAACCAUCAGAGCAGAGGAGGAAAGACUCACUACCUCAGAAAAAUCUCAAAGAAUAGUCCAAUUUCCUGCUUGCCAAAGCAUAAUCUGCCUUUUGGUGCAUUACUUGGUCAAUUCAGGGUUGAGGAGACUGUUGGGGGGCAUUUAUAAUGUAUGAAAGUUAAGGAAGGGGGUGAGGAUGUGGGUUGGGACAGGUAGUACCUAAAGAGGAGCGAAGGGAUUUAUACAACAUUUUUAUCAUGUUACAAAACAGUAUCAUGAAUGGCCUCCUUUUUAGUUCAACUGUUUCUUUAAAAUGCAUUUACUGAUUAAAAAUAAGAACUGACCAAUAGCUCCAAGUGUCACACACCAGAACAUUAAGCCUAAGUCCUCAAUUCAUAAGUUAUCAUUCUAGAUAAGUUUCUUUACAAUGGAAUACUUUCUGUGGAAUCAUUAUAAUUCUGUUGUAUGGAACUAUCAAGCUAAGAGUCACUAAACUUUCUUCAAAAGGUUGUGUGAAAUAUGACAGCUUUCUAAAUUAAUUUGUAUAGUCAUUUAAAAUUUUUUCUUCUCUGGCAACUGUCCAACUGGAAUCCAGAUUUAAAGUGAUAAAAGCUCUAAGUUUCUUGCAGUCUUUUUCUCAGCUUAGUUCCAGAGAGAAAAAAGCUAAUUUUCCUAAGGACACAGCAAGAAUAUUCAUUAAGGAUAUUUUCUAAAACCCACACUUGAGAAAACCACCCAAUGAGUCAAAAAUAUAUAUAUAUAAUAUAUAUUUUAUAUAUAUGUAAUAUAUAUUUAUGUUAUAUAUUAUAUAUAGAACAAUUCCAUUACAUAUAUAAUAUAUAAAUAUAUAUAUUAUAUAUACAUAUAUUGUAUAUGAAUAUAUAUUAUAUAUACAUAUAAUUAUAUAUAUAUAAAUAUAUAUUAUAUAACAUAUAAUGAAUAUAUAUUAUAUAUAUAAUGGAAUUGUUCUGGAAGUAAAAUGGGGUAGGAAUGGGGUUCUGAGAAUAGGCAAUAACAUUUUCACCAGUCUCUUGGGAAAUUGUAGAACUCAUGUAAAAAUUUCUUGGUCAUGAUAUGUCUCAAUGGCAGCCUCAGUAAAUAAAAAUGUAGCCUCAGAUAUUAUAUUUAAAGAUGUAGUAAAUCUAGCCCAAAAUAGGACAAUUUGGAAGAUUUAAGUAUUACAUAUUUUUUAAAUGUCUGUGUUCUAAAUGUGAAAUGCACUUUGCUCAUUUUAAAGUUCAUAAUACUAACUGCCAACUGACACCACUUCUCGCUCCCUUUCUUCUCUUGAACUCAUUUUUCUCCCUUUUUAUUUACCCCCUUCAAAUUACUUCAUUCUUUGGAAAUAACUAUUACCAAGCCCCAUUCUUCAAAAUAAGUAAACAUUGUAUAGAGCCAAGUUCUGCAAAAGAUCCAUACCAGUUCACUCGUGUGCGACUGUGGACAGGUAAGUCACUUUGGUCUCUAUGAACCUCAGUUUUCCAGAUCUUUGAAAUGAGCACUUGGAUGCCUAUCCUUGCUUCCACACAAGUGUUUUUUUUUUUUUUUUUUUUUUUUUGUGAGAAUCGAUUGAAAUAGUAUAUGAAGUGGUUUGAAAAUAGGUACAAACUAUUGACAUUUCAAUGUCAGAGAGUGAUACCUGUAGUAGUAUAGGCAAAGGUCCAACCCCAUCGAAAGGCUUAAACAUUUACCUUUUCUGAAAAACUAUUGAAAUAUAAAGAGAGUCCCCAGUCACAGGGGCAACUUCUGUAACCAAAUCCAGAUCUGAGGAAACUCCUGUAACCCCAUUUGGGGUUUCUUUCUAAGCCAAUAGGGUUACAGGUUGGUACAGUGACACAUUGAGAAUGGGGCUACAAAUACUUUUCCCACCAUCUAGGAUGAAAUACACGAAAUCCUGUUGAAAUCUUGGUUUUUAUGCCUUUGCUCAUCAGAAUAAACGUAAAUGCUGAAAAACAAAUAACCUCCUGAUCCACUGUCUUGCCUCCUGGUGAGAAAUGAUUCUAUCCCCUGUUUAUUGGGAAAUUUCCAAAGUUGUUCAUCACUUAAAUGCCGUAUUCAAAGGGAACAUGGAAGGAUGAAGCGGAGAAAGUGCCUUCGAGACAUUCACACAUUUCUCUGGACUCAGUCUGUUAACAUAUCAGGGAGCUUGUCAGAUCACACCUUUUUGCCUUGGAAAUCCUACAGAUUUCCUGUACGCCUUCAUAUCUGAUUCUUCCCUAAAACCUUUGGGUAUGAUUUCCUCCCUGGUCUUGAUAAUGUCCUGCAGUCUGUGUUUUAUAAUUAUUCUUUGUAUUUAUUGAAUCUAGACUUUAAGUUAUUCAGAGAUCAGACCAGAACCUUAGAGUUUCUAAACUGUAUGUGGAUAUUAAAUAAUAUUAAUAAUGAAAGAGCUACCAAAAUAGUCUAUAUUGUGUGAACAAUCUCUUGGGAUAUUAGACGUGUUUAAAGACCAGUGUUGCUGCUAUUUUUAAUAUUUUGGUUAAUUUAAGUGAAAUGUACAUAUUUUAAUUUGAAGAUUUAUCUUGCCCAUCAGAAUGUGAAGAUAUACUUGCAUAUAUUUUGACAUAUUUCAUGGAAAAUAAAAAUGAUAAUCCACUUUGUGAGUGUAAGUGAAUGUAUUCAUAUGUAUGUUAUUAUAAAUGAUUUUUGUUUGCACUGAUGAUGAAAUGAGAGUUUUGGGGGCUUUUUAUACAUUUAUAUCGACUGGUCUCUAAAUCUCCUAUUUUGUUUUCUUAUCAUUUUUGAAAUACAGUUCCCAUUACAUGAGUUUUAAAUAGAUUGGUGUUUCAUUUUGUAUUAUGCUACUACUAGAUGUUGAUUCUCUGGUAUUGUAAAAUAAAAUGUGCUCCAAAAACCCAAA